GUUUCCGGCCGAGGCUGCGGCCAUGGCAGCAUCUUCCCUGACGGUCACCUUAGGGCGGCUGGCGUCCGCGUGCAGCCACAGCAUCCUGAGACCUUCGGGGCCCGGAGCAGCCUCCCUUUGGUCUGCUUCUCGAAGGUUCAAUUCACAGAGCACUUCAUAUCUACCAGGAUAUGUUCCUAAAACAUCCCUGAGUUCACCACCUUGGCCAGAAGUUGUUCUGCCAGACCCAGUUGAGGAGACCAGACACCAUGCAGAGGUCGUGAAGAAGGUGAAUGAGAUGAUCGUCACGGGGCAGUAUGGCAGGCUCUUUGCCGUGGUGCACUUUGCCAGCCGCCAGUGGAAGGUGACCUCUGAAGACCUGAUCUUAAUUGGAAAUGAACUAGACCUUGCGUGUGGAGAGAGAAUUCGACUGGAGAAGGUCCUGCUGGUUGGGGCAGACAACUUCACGCUGCUUGGCAAGCCACUCCUCGGAAAGGAUCUUGUUCGAGUAGAAGCCACAGUCAUUGAAAAGACAGAAUCAUGGCCAAGAAUCAUUAUGAGAUUCAGGAAAAGGAAAAACUUCAAGAAGAAAAGAAGUAAGUUAGAGAAAGUACCGCUGGGCCCUGUUGCACGGUGCUGGUUGCCCAGGCGCAUGCGGACGGAGGGUGUGGGGCACGUGGGUCUCGGGACAGGAAGCCCAGGCAGGUCUCAACCUGGCUGCCACUGCCCACUUGCCACCCUCAUCCUAGAGGGAGCACCCAGAGGGUCCAGCCUCGCUCCCCUUCUCCUCCACGCUCCACGCGUGACCCCACCUCGCUCCCCUUCUCCUCCACGCUCCGCACGUGACCCCACCUCGCUCCCCUUCUCCUCCACCCUCCGCGCGUGACCCCACCUCGCUCCCCUUCUCCUCCACCCUCCGCGCAUGACCCCACCUCGCUCCCCUUCUCCUCCACCCUCCGCGCGUGACCCCACCUCGCUCCCCUUCUCCUCCACCCUCCGCGCGUGACCCCACCUCGCUCCCCUUCUCCUCCACCCUCCGCGCGUGACCCCACCUCGCUCCCCUUCUCCUCCACCCUCCGCGCGUGACCCCACCUCGCUCCCCUUCUCCUCCACCCUCCGCGCGUGACCCCACCUCGCUCCCCUUCUCCUCCACCCUCCGCGCGUGACCCCACCUCGCUCCCCUUCUCCUCCACCCUCCGCGCGUGACCCCACCUCGCUCCCCUUCUCCUCCACCCUCCGCGCGUGACCCCACCUCGCUCCCCUUCUCCUCCACCCUCCGCGCGUGACCCACCUCGCUCCCCUUCUCCUCCACCCUCCGCGCGUGAACCCACCUCGCUCCCCUUCUCCUCCACCCUCCGCGCGUGAACCCACCUCGCUCCCCUUCUCCACCCUCCACGCGUGACCCCACCUCGCUCCCCUUCUCCUCCACCCUCCACGCAUGACCCCACUUUGUUCCAACCCAUGACGCCUAGCACUGUCCCCAAAGCAGCAGUGAAUCCGCAAGCAGGUGUAGGGCUGUCCUAGCAGGUCUGCACUGAGGACAUCCCCCAUAGUGGGCAUCCUGAGGGAUGGCACCCACGGGGCAUGGGCCACAUAGCUGAGCGGCUGCAGAAUUCUGUCCCUCACAGCUCUUGCUAUAACUGCAGUUGCCGGCCUAAACCACCAACAGUGGGCAUAGUUAAAUAUACCCAGAAUACUGGUAUUGGCUGUCACCUUAGAGUCAUCUGGGUAGGGGAGCCUCUCAUGUACCUUCUGACACUUCCAGGUAGCCUCAAGGUCACUCAGGUGGGGCCAUCCUCCCACGCACUCCAGAAGUCACAGCAUAGACAGUGUGGGAGGAGAGGUGAGGUGCCAGCGCAGGGCACUCCUGGCCAUGAGGCGUCUGGUGUCCCAGCCUCUGCACCUGCCAACAGAGUGAACGAACAAGCUAGCGAGGCAGUCAGUGCACACCUGGAGAUAAACACGGCCAUGUGCAGCAGGGGACGUUGCCGGGGUCGCGCUGGCUGGGGAGGGCUGUGUGCAGAGCCCCUGCUGUAACUGAUGACAACAGUCAGGGUCUGUGGUCAAGCCUGUGACAUCCUUUCUUUCAGUCGUCACGACCCCGCAGACUGUCCUCCGGAUAAACAGCAUUGAGAUUGCUCCGUGUUUGUUGUGAUUACCGAGUUAAUACUUACAAAA